GUUUUCCGGCGCCGGCCCUAGGUCCCGGCAGCGGUGGUGACGGCGGUGCCGGAGGUUGUCCUUGGCAGGUUUUCCUCGGCGCUUCUCCAUGGAGGAGGCGGUGCGAACGGCUUCAGCCCCGAAUGCUCGCAUCUCCCACUGGACGGCGACGAAGGCGGUGGCCGUGCGAGCGCAGGACUGGGCGGCCUGUGUGGGGGUGUGAGCCGCGGUGCCCAAGGCUGCGCCGGCGAGGGGAAGCCGCGCGGCCGGCCGGCCGACUAGGGUGAGGUCGCCACUCCUUCCUUUCAGGCAAGCGCGAAGGGGCUGACUUGGUGGCGAGCCAGCCCGCCUUGUGUCGGAGAAGGGUUCUUCGGGCAACUUUCCUUUCCGGGUGUUCUGAAGCGGUUUUCCUGUAAUCCUCAGUGAGGAAACCCACCGUGAAUCGGAUUGCCGUUCAGUCCCACGGAAGCCUGGCUCGUUGGCCAUGUCGGGGACGCAUGUUCAUUAAGUUCAUUAAAAUAAUUUCAUUUGUCUUGGCUGGAGCUACUCGGCCAGGGUUUAAGACUUUAAAUGAGAAUAAAGGGUGGUAUUUACGAGGAAAUGAGAGUGAAUAAGUCAUCUCUAACCUCUCCCAGCCUUUUUUUCAUAAGAGAGACCAUAUUAAACUUACAUGCUCUCCCGGCUGUGAUAGACCUUCAGUUACAGAGAGAGGGAGCAGAGUGGGACCAGGUCUGAGAAUAGUGAAGCAACUCAUUCCUUUCAGGACAUUCCCUCUGAUGUCCUAUUUUCAAACUUUCAUCUGUCAACUGAGUUUAUGAGUUGGCCAUUUGGAAAAACAAUUGCAGUCUUGGUAAGCCUCUGCUUCCUGUCUGGCCUCGAGGAUUGAGCCCUCCAGAUACCAUGGUCCUCAUGUUCUCCAAAGGCCACCGGUACCAUACUGCACGCCCCAGCAGACACCUCUCUGCAAGAAUUGUUACCCUCUGAUAAAUAAUGUGAAAUCUGCCUUCUCUCAGCACAUCCCUGAAUAGGCUAAAUAAAUAAAUUAGCAUAUGCUUAUGUGCACCUAUUGCUAAGAAGAAAAUGUAUGGGUUUGAAGACUGCUUCAUUCUGCCUCUAGUACCAGCGGUUUCUCUGUUCUGUGAUCAAUGUGAUUCACAGGAACUCCUUAAGUAACAAACGAAAUGAGCCAGGGGCGUGGAAAAUAUGACUUCUAUAUUGGUCUGGGAUUGGCUAUGAGCUCCAGCAUUUUCAUUGGAGGAAGUUUCAUUUUGAAAAAAAAGGGCCUCCUUCGACUUGCCAGGAAAGGCUCUAUGAGAGCAGGUCAAGGUGGCCAUGCAUAUCUUAAGGAAUGGUUGUGGUGGGCUGGACUGCUGUCAAUGGGAGCUGGUGAGGUGGCCAACUUCGCUGCGUAUGCGUUUGCACCAGCCACUCUAGUGACUCCACUAGGAGCUCUCAGCGUGCUAGUAAGUGCCAUUCUUUCUUCAUACUUUCUCAAUGAAAGACUUAAUCUUCAUGGGAAAAUUGGGUGUUUGCUAAGUAUUCUAGGAUCUACAGUUAUGGUCAUUCAUGCUCCAAAGGAAGAGGAGAUUGAGACUUUAAAUGAAAUGUCUCACAAGCUAGGUGAUCCAGGUUUUGUGGUCUUUGCAACCCUUGUGGUCAUUGUGGCCUUGAUAUUAAUCUUCGUGGUGGGUCCUCGCCAUGGACAGACAAACAUUCUUGUGUACAUAACAAUCUGCUCUGUAAUCGGCGCGUUUUCAGUCUCCUGUGUGAAGGGCCUGGGCAUUGCUAUCAAGGAGCUGUUUGCAGGGAAGCCUGUGCUGCGGCAUCCCCUGGCUUGGAUUCUGCUGCUGAGCCUCAUCGUCUGUGUGAGCACACAGAUUAAUUACCUAAAUAGGGCCCUGGAUAUAUUCAACACUUCCAUUGUGACUCCAAUAUAUUAUGUAUUCUUUACAACAUCAGUUUUAACUUGUUCAGCUAUUCUUUUUAAGGAGUGGCAAGAUAUGCCUGUUGACGAUGUCAUUGGUACUUUGAGUGGCUUCUUUACAAUCAUUGUGGGGAUAUUCUUGUUGCAUGCCUUUAAAGACGUCAGCUUUAGUCUAGCAAGUCUGCCUGUGUCUUUUCGAAAAGACGAGAAAGCAAUGAAUGGCAAUCUCUCUAAUAUGUAUGAAGUUCUUAAUAAUAAUGAAGAAAGCUUAACCUGUGGAAUCGAACAACACACUGGUGAAAAUGUCUCCCGAAGAAAUGGAAAUCUGACAGCUUUUUAAGGUGUAAUUAAAGGUUAAUCUGUGAUUGUUAUGAAGUGAAUUUGAAUAUCAUCAGAAUGUGUCUGAAAAAACAUUGUCCUCAAAUAAUGUUCUUUAAAGGCAAUCUUUUUAAAGAUUUCACUAAUUUGGACCAAGAAAUUACUUUUCUUGUAUUUAAACAAACAAUGGUAGCUCACUAAAAUGACCUCAGCACAUGACGAUUUCUAUUAACAUUUUAUUGUUGUAGAAGUAUUUUACAUUUUCAUCCCUUCUCCAAAAGCCGAAUGCACUAAUGACAGUUUUAAGUCUAUGAAAAUGCUUUAUUUUUUCAUUGGUGAUGAAAGUCUGAAAUGUGCAUUUGUCAUCCCCACUCCAUCAAUCCCUGACCAUGUAAGGCUUUUUUAUUUUAAAAAAACAGAGUUAUCCCAAUACAUUAUCCUGUGAUUUACCUUACCUACAAAAGUGGCUCCUGUUUGUUUGAUGAUGAUUGGUUUUAUUUUUGAAAUAUUUAUUAAGGGAAAACUAAGUUACUGAAUGAAGGAACCUCUUUCUUACAAAACAAAAAAAAGGGCAGAAAUCACCCCAAGGAACGAUUUCUCAGGUUGAGAUGAUCACCGUGAAUCCGGCUUCCUCUGAGCAUUCGAUGGCCUUAGCACCUCAUCAAGCCAGCACAUCCUGCCUGCUGUUGCAGCCUGGCUGGGUUUAUUCUUCAGUUACCCUAAUCCCAUGAUGCCUGGAACCUUGAUUACCGUUUUACAUCAGCUCUUGUACUUUUCAGUAUAUUUUCAUAAUGAGUUAUAUUGUCAUUUAGACUUUGAACAGCUCUGGGAAAUAGAAGACUAGGGUUGUUUCUUAAAGUUUAGCUCAUGUUAUAAUAAAAAGUUGAAAUGAAGUUCUUAUUCUAAAAGUCUGAAUGCUUAGAACAAACUUAACAUGUUUAUAGAAUAUGGUCUCUUUGUACCAAGUACUUUGCUUAAGAGCUCCUUUGGGCCACUACAUAUUUUGGUUUCUAGAAAAUGUUUGUUUGUUUAUGAAGAAGUUGAUGGAAAACUGCAAACAUAUGCAGAAAAGGUAGAAUAAUAAAAAAGGUCUAAUGAACUCCAUUCAGCUUUGAACCUAUCCACUCAUAACCAUUGACUGGCCUUUAAAAAAAAGUAUUGGCAGAAUUAAUUUCCACCUAGGUGAUGGGAAGAAAGUGUUCGCCUGUUCCAGCCUGUGGCUCCUGCCUGGAGGUUACCCAGUGGUGCGCCAGCGCCAAGCCAUCACUCCCCGAGGGCCUCCCCUGCCAAUGGUGCUGGUAUCCCAUGCAGCUCACCACUGGCUGCGUGGAAACUCCCUUUUUUCCAACUGUAUUAUUGGCCUUCUAAGGAGCUGUUUUAGAUGUUUUUUCUAACUGCCUCCUCCCAUGCCAUUUUAAUACUACAGAUGUACUACGUAUCUGUUUAUAUACUGUACCUACAUCUGUGCUUUGUACAUAAAAGAACCAGUUUUCUCCCCCUUGAGGACAGAGACUCAUUUGAACAUGCAUAGGUUAAUAAAUAAUAAAUUCUUAUUUAACA